AGUCUGGGCGUAGAGGGUGCAGGGAGCAGACGGGAGGAUCUCAGGCCAGGGACGAUGGCGGCUCUGCAGGAGAAGAAGACGUGUGGCCAGCGCAUGGAGGAGUUCCAGCGUUACUGCUGGAACCCGGACACGGGGCAGAUGCUGGGCCGCACCCUGUCCCGGUGGGUGUGGAUCAGCCUGUACUACGUGGCCUUCUACGUGGUGAUGACUGGGCUCUUCGCCCUGUGCCUCUAUGUGCUGAUGCAGACAGUGGACCCGUACACACCGGACUACCAAGACCAGCUACGGUCACCAGGGGUAACCUUAAGGCCGGAUGUUUACGGGGAGAAAGGCCUGGAAAUUGUCUACAACGUCUCUGAUAACAGAACCUGGGCAGACCUCACACAGACUCUCCACGCCUUCCUAGCAGGCUACUCUCCAGCAGCCCAGGAGGACAGCAUCAACUGCACCUCCGAGCAGUACUUCUUCCAGGAGAGUUUCCGCGCUCCCAACCACACCAAGUUCUCCUGCAAGUUCACGGCAGAUAUGCUGCAGAACUGCUCAGGCCUGGCGGAUCCCAACUUCGGCUUUGAAGAAGGAAAGCCAUGUUUUAUUAUUAAAAUGAACAGGAUCGUCAAGUUCCUCCCCAGCAACGGCUCGGCCCCCAGAGUGGACUGCGCCUUCCUGGACCAGCCCCGCGAGCUCGGCCAGCCGCUGCAGGUCAAGUACUACCCUCCCAACGGCACCUUCAGUCUGCACUACUUCCCUUAUUACGGGAAGAAAGCCCAGCCCCACUACAGCAACCCCCUGGUGGCAGCGAAGCUCCUCAACAUCCCCAGGAACGCUGAGGUCGCCAUCGUGUGCAAGGUCAUGGCGGAGCACGUGACCUUCAACAAUCCCCACGACCCGUAUGAAGGGAAAGUGGAGUUCAAACUCAAGAUUGAGAAGUGAAACGGUUUGCGCAGGGGUCCUGGGCACGCCUGCGGGGUCGCUCAAGGACACCCUCCUGGUUGGGCUUACCUUGCCCGUCAGUUCCCUGCCAAAUCAUCCCCAAAGUGGUUUGGAGCAACGGUGUUGUCAGUGUGCGAACUCCAGAGAAGCGCCCACAUCUGAAGGACCUGCUCGCGAGUAUCAGUUCUUCCUUGUU